AGCGUGUGCAGCGGCGGCGGCGGAAGUGGCCGGCGAGCCCGGUCCCCGCCGGCACCAUGCUUCCCUUGUCACUGCUGAAGACGGCUCAGAAUCACCCCAUGUUGGUGGAGCUGAAAAAUGGGGAGACGUACAAUGGACACCUGGUGAGCUGCGACAACUGGAUGAACAUUAACCUGCGAGAAGUCAUCUGCACGUCCAGGGACGGGGACAAGUUCUGGCGGAUGCCCGAGUGCUACAUCCGCGGCAGCACCAUCAAGUACCUGCGCAUCCCCGACGAGAUCAUCGACAUGGUCAAGGAGGAGGUGGUGGCCAAGGGCCGCGGCCGCGGAGGCCUGCAGCAGCAGAAGCAGCAGAAAGGCCGCGGCAUGGGCGGCGCUGGCCGAGGUGUGUUUGGUGGCCGGGGCCGAGGUGGGAUCCCGGGCACAGGCAGAGGCCAGCCAGAGAAGAAGCCUGGCAGACAGGCGGGCAAACAGUGAGCGCCCACCCAGACCGGCUGCUGCGCCCCCUCCUGCCAGGGUGGCGAUUCCGCUCCACAGUCUCGGACGGAUCUGCUCAGAAAGGAAGAGGCAGGCGCCAGGGGGAACCCCCUUCGUGUUUUGUGACCCUCCCUUUUAGGUGAAGCCCCUUUUUCUUGCUAAAACCGGCAAUUCUCCGGUUAGAAAUGUUACUUGGUGUUUUUUGGUUUUGUGAAACGGCCGUCCCAAAACUGGCUGGAUUCCUAGAAGAGUCUGUGUUGAAGGCAUCUUUCAAGCCCUCGCUCUGGUUCUCAGGGCAGCAUUUUCCAGGCGGGUUUGUUUUGCAUUUCUUGGAGCCUCUCCGAGCAGCAACCAGACGGGAGAUUUUUAUUUUAAGCUGUUCAUGCUGGGACUGACAGCCUGCAGGGUUUCCUUGGGCGCGGCCCCAAAAUUGCCUUCAAAACAAACCCGGGACGGUUGAAAGCCUUCGAACCGUGCAGGGGAUGCCUCGGGCCCUGGCCCUUCGCUUCCUCUCUUGUGUUAUGGAAAUAAAAACAAAUAAAACUACACACUGCACAUCCACUGUUCCUUUUGAGCUUCUGGGUGCACCUAGCGGGUCUCCUGCCCUCUGUCCAUCGCUGGACUCUCAGGAAAUCCCCGUUCCCGUAAGGGAAGCUUCCUUUUGAGAGUUCUCACCAGGUGUCAGCGGCACAGUGAGGCACUGAUGUCCUUUUACAAAAGGCAAGACCAGCAUCUGGACAGUGGGGGCUCUUGAGAGUCCCCGGCGCCCCCCACACCAGGUUGUCCUAUAACCCUCUCCCCUCUGUGGAGACGUUAAUGCCAAGGGGUGUGUGGGGAGGGAAGUCCCAGGCAGGGGCCACGCAUGGUCCCCAUCACCCCCUCCUGGGUGGCCUGGACUCCAUCAUCUAUCCUCAUCUGUCCACACUGGCGUUCACACAGAGAAGACAGGACAGGAAUCCCCUCGGAAGAUGCUCAUGGAAGAUUCUCACGAGGCUCCUGCCCCCUUUCUGAGCCAGGCCGGGUUUGCCACUCCUCGGGCGCGCACCUGAGACACUGAGUCAGCGCUUUCGAGAAAGGCUCCGGGUAGCAUCUGUGGACCGUGAAGAAACCAGAGGGAAGCCCUGAGCCAGGCAGCGGCCCGUCCCCCUGCAUAGCCUUCUCUUCAGGGUCCUCGUUCGGAGACCUAUUUUGAGAGGUGAUUGGAAUAAAAGGUCCCGUCCGUGAGGAA